AGGCCAGCCGGCGCCAUUUUGAAAGUGGAGUCGCCUGCCCCUGCCGCUGCCGCCGCCGCCGUCGCUGUCGUAGUCGCCGCCGCCGCUGCCGGAGAAAGAGCACGAGCGGGGAAGCCCCAGAGUGAAAUCUAGCAUCCUGCCGGCUGGUCUGCCCGCCCCUCCUUCCUUUUCCCCCCGGCCCCCGUCCCCUCCCCCCGCAGGUGCCAUCCGCCGCCAUCCGCCCUCUCUACCCCCCCAUCCCCAGGUGAGGGGGGUGAGUUCAGGAAGCGGAGACCCCGAGGAACCCAGCAGGGUCACCAUUUGCAGCGCAACAUGGCAGGAGCUGGAGGAGGGAAUGAUAUUCAGUGGUGUUUUUCUCAGGUGAAAGGAGCAGUAGAUGAUGAUGUAGCAGAAGCAGAUAUAAUUUCUACAGUAGAAUUUAAUCAUUCUGGAGAAUUACUAGCAACAGGAGAUAAAGGUGGUAGAGUUGUCAUCUUUCAACAGGAGCAGGAGAACAAAAUCCAGUCUCAUAGCAGAGGAGAAUAUAAUGUUUACAGCACCUUCCAGAGCCAUGAACCAGAGUUUGACUACUUGAAAAGUUUAGAAAUAGAAGAAAAGAUCAACAAAAUUAGGUGGUUACCCCAGAAAAAUGCUGCUCAGUUUUUAUUGUCUACCAAUGAUAAAACAAUAAAAUUAUGGAAAAUCAGUGAAAGGGACAAAAGACCAGAAGGGUAUAACUUGAAAGAGGAGGAUGGAAGGUAUAGAGAUCCUACUACAGUUACUACACUACGAGUGCCAGUCUUUAGGCCUAUGGAUCUAAUGGUUGAGGCCAGUCCACGAAGAAUAUUUGCCAAUGCUCAUACAUAUCACAUCAACUCAAUUUCUAUUAAUAGUGAUUAUGAAACAUAUUUAUCUGCAGAUGAUUUGCGGAUUAAUCUUUGGCAUCUGGAAAUUACAGACAGGAGUUUUAACAUUGUGGAUAUCAAGCCUGCCAAUAUGGAAGAGCUAACAGAGGUGAUUACAGCAGCAGAAUUUCAUCCAAACAGCUGUAACACAUUUGUAUACAGCAGCAGUAAAGGAACUAUUCGGCUAUGUGACAUGAGGGCAUCUGCCCUCUGUGAUAGACAUUCUAAAUUGUUUGAAGAACCUGAAGAUCCCAGUAACAGGUCAUUUUUUUCCGAAAUCAUCUCCUCUAUUUCGGAUGUAAAAUUCAGCCAUAGUGGUCGAUAUAUGAUGACUAGAGACUAUUUGUCAGUCAAAAUUUGGGACUUAAAUAUGGAAAACAGGCCUGUGGAAACAUACCAGGUGCAUGAAUACCUCAGAAGUAAACUCUGUUCACUGUAUGAAAAUGACUGCAUAUUUGACAAAUUUGAAUGUUGUUGGAAUGGAUCUGACAGUGUUGUCAUGACUGGAUCUUACAAUAAUUUCUUCAGAAUGUUUGACAGAAACACAAAGCGAGACAUAACCCUAGAAGCAUCGCGGGAAAACAAUAAGCCUCGCACAGUUCUGAAGCCUCGCAAAGUCUGUGCAAGUGGCAAGCGAAAGAAAGAUGAAAUAAGUGUUGACAGCCUAGACUUCAAUAAGAAAAUCCUUCACACAGCCUGGCACCCCAAGGAAAAUAUCAUUGCCGUAGCUACUACAAACAAUCUGUAUAUAUUUCAAGACAAAGUGAAUUAGGGUUGGCAUUCCUAGCAGAAGAACCCACUUCCUGCUUAGUUGAGAUAGUUGAAUCUAGCAUUCGUUCCUAUAAAAGAGAGAGGUCCAUUGUGGCGCCCCUUUCCAGUGUUUGACAGUGUGCCAUUCGACAACACAUUGUUAUAGCUACAUGGAGAAAGCUCUGUGGAUUCAUCACUGUGGUGUUCUCCAUGUCUGCUAGCCAUUUAGGUAAGGGUAGGGCACUUUUAAUUUAAAUGACUUCUUGCACCAUCUUGCCUAAUGGACUAGAUUGGACUGUAUCAACAUUGAUUUACUCCACUUUUUAUGCCUUCCAUUGUGAUGACGUCAAACACAGUGAAAGCCUUCAGUCAUGCUAUGGGAUUUAAUUGUGUAUCCUCAUUACUGUAUCAUUUGUGGGGUACACCCCUUCCCCCUUUUUUUAAAUUAAAUACAGCUCAUUCUUACUGUGGCUUGUAGCAUUCCUCCUCUUCUGGCCUCCUGGACUGCUCCCCUUCAUCUCUUACCCUUGCCCCCUCCACCCGGUCUUGGUGGUGGUAUAUUAAAAAAAGAAAGAAUGAAAGCACACAAAAUGAGUCAGUUUGGGGUCAGUGGUAUAAAGGGGGUAUAUGUUGCAAACAAAUGUUUUAGUAACAGUUGGCUGUAAUCACUCCUCGCCGUGUCUGGCACUGAAAAUAAGGAAAAAAAACCUACUACUGAAUAAAAGUGACAAAGAAUGGAGAAUCUGGUUUUCUUUUUCUUUUUAACCUACCUCUUGUAGCCAAUAUUUUGUGUCAUACCUUUGGGCACAGUGAAACAAAAUGGGUUUUCAUUGUUUAUUGGUAUUUUUGUUAAUUAUUUUUAACAAGUGUUCUUUUACAUGCAGGAGGAGAGGUAUUGGUUCUCUAUGAACAUAUUUUGAAUAUAGGUUUUAUUAAGGAUUUCACAAUCUAUAAAUGCUACUAGUUUUUUUUUUUUUUUUUACCAUCAUGAGGGUAUUGGAUACAUUGUGUCUCUAUUUAACUCAUUAUGUGUUAAUGAAAUUGUUGUAAAUGGGAACCAAAUUUGUAGAACUUAAUUUCUACUUUUUAGAGUGCUUAAUUUCAUUUUUGCCUUACUAAAUAGUCAAAGACUUAUAAAACAUUUUUAACAAGUUAGAACUUUUUUGUUAUUCAGUCAUAUAAAAUAGCAGAAAACUAACAUCAAGUGACACUGCACUAAAUACUUUUUUUGUAUUUUACUGCUAUCAAAUCAGAAUGAAAUAUACUUUACCAUAGAUAUUUUUCUUCUAUUUUUGGUUUUCCAAAGCUAUAUGAAAGACAAAUUUUUAAAGGUACAGCGUUCAAAAAGUGCUUAAUGAACUCCAACAGCUGCCUCAAAUAAAAAUCUGUAUAUGAAUACAUUUUCCCUAAGCGGUGAUACAUUAUCCAAAGAUGAAGAGUGCUCCUAUUUUUAAUAGGUAGAAUGUACCUUUGUCAGUCUUGCAGAAACUUUAAUGGAGAAGAAAUGGACUUUAUUUUUGAAAGGUGAAAUGAACAGGCAUUUAUAUUAUUAGAGAAUGGUAGUCUUAUUUUGGUGGAACAUAAUGUAACAACCUUGAAUUUCAGAGGACUCUGAGUGCUUCUAUGUCCACUACCUAUUGUUCUAUUCUUCAAUAAUGAAAAAGAAUUCAACGAGCCGACCGUGAUUCCCUCUACUACAAAUAUUAUGUCUUGUAAGUUAGCAUUUUUAGCACACAGGAGAAAUUUUAUGUAAUAAAAUUACUGUAUCUUUUGGAUUUAACAAAUUUGUAUUUGAAACACAUUCUAUGUCUGAUAAUUCUUAAUGGCACUUUUACUAAUUUAUUUGGGGAUCUUGGGUACAUUCUUAAUUUGUGUUUAUUCUUCACGCUUGACUUGCAAGUGGGAUAUUCCCCUGCCACAAGUGUCAAACAGUGAUAUUCUUCCUGUGUUGUGACUGGACAGUUUUCCAGAUCUUUUUUGGGAGAUUUUCCUACAGCUUGGUUGUAUGUCUUGAGAUAACACCACCAAACAGCUCUCAGAAAUUCUUUUUUGAUUGAUCAGUAGCUAUGAUGAUUCUCCUCCAUGACACUAAGGAUUAGUUUAUAUAUUUAAGAGAAAUAAUUGCUAAAAUUAAAAUGCCUCUAUCAAGGAAUGCUAUUAUAAAUUAUUGUUAACAUUCUCAAGUAUUAAUUUUUUAAUUUCAUUGGUGUAGCAAACUCUAAGCCCAGCCACUCAUUUUACAUGGCCAUGGUUAAUCUUUUUAUUAAUAAAAAUUAUACUUAGAAUAAA